GCCAUCUCGCAUAUUCUCAACGGCUGUGCGUGUCCUUAAAAGUCCCUGGGAAGCGGCCGGGCGCGGUGGCUCACCCCUGUAAUCCCAGCAGUUUGGGAGGCCGAGGCGGGUGCAUCAUCUAAGGUCAAGAGUUCGAGACAAGUCUGGCCAAGAUGGUGAAACCCCCGUCUCUACGAAAAAUACAAAAAUUAGCCGGGCGUGGUGGCUCAUGCCUGUAAUCUCAGCUACUCGGGAGGCUGAGACAGGAGAAUUGCUUGAACCCGGGAGGCGGAGGUUGCAGUGACCCGAGAUCUCGCCACCGCACUCCAGCCUGGGCGACAGAGCGGGACUCCACCUCAAAAAAAAAAAAAAAAAGUACCUGGGAAGCAUGGCCGACAGUGGGGUUGGGUUAUAUUCGCGGACGUGAACUGUGGCGCGCUGUGCAUGUUCACUGGGGUGGGGGGUCCCAGGCGCUCAGAGGAGACUGCAGAAUAGGCCCGAGAGGAGAGGGGAGUUCGUUUCGCCGCCGUCUUCAUGGGCGAGCUUCCUAACCGCCACCUCGCCCCGGAGCAAUUGGCACAUUGUAUUGAACGCUGCUGUUCUUCUUACUCUUCCUCCUUGUGAUCUCUAAUAGAACUGUUAGAAGCAGGACAGAGCCAAAUUGGCUUGGACCAAGUCCGUCUUGGGCACCCCAGGCUGGCCUGUUCUCUCCACCCUCCUCACACUCCGGGGGGAAACUGACUCUACUCUGUGAUGCCAAGACAGAUGGGAGUUUCCUUGUACACCACUUUCUCUCCUUCUAUCUCAAAGCUAAUUGUAAAGUCUGCUUUGUGGCACUCAUCCAGUCCUUCAGCCACUACAGUAUCGUGGGACAGAAGCUGGGUGUCAGCCUGACCAUGGCGCGGGAGCGUGGGCAGCUUGUGUUCCUUGAGGGACUCAAGUCUGCAGUGGACGUCGUCUUCCAGGCUCAAAAGGAGCCACACCCCCUGCAGUUUCUCAGGGAGGCUAAUGCUGGGAACUUGAAACCAUUGUUUGAGUUUGUACGGGAGGCCCUGAAGCCAGUAGACAGUGGAGAGGCUCGGUGGACGUACCCGGUGCUGUUGGUGGACGACCUCAGUGUGCUCCUGAGCCUGGGCAUGGGGGCGGUGGCUGUGCUAGACUUCAUUCACUACUGCAGAGCCACCGUGUGCUGGGAACUAAAGGGAAACAUGGUGGUCCUUGUGCACGACAGUGGAGAUGCGGAGGAUGAGGAGAAUGACAUCCUGCUGAAUGGCCUCAGUCAUCAGAGCCAUCUGAUACUGCGGGCUGAGGGCCUGGCCACUGGCUUCUGCAGGGAUGUGCACGGGCAGCUGAGGAUCCUGUGGAGGAGACCAUCGCAGCCCGCAGUCCACCGGGAUCAGAGCUUCACUUACCAGUAUAAGAUACAGGACAAAAGCGUGUCCUUUUUUGCCAAAGGAAUGUCUCCUGCUGUUCUGUGACCUGAUUUCGGAGCAGCUGAAGCUACAUAGGACUGUUUUUGGACGUGGAAGAUAGAGCAACAUAGCAAGAAUGGGUCUUUCUCCUCUGUAGUAAUAUUUCAGGCUGGACCGGCGACUCCACUGUGACCAGAGGGUUGAGUGCUGCAGUGAUGGCAUGCCUUGGCUGCCCUGGGCCCUGUUCAGAAAACACAAGGGACCACAAUCCUGCCUUUGCUGAGAGAGAGGCUGGAUGCUAGACCCAAGUGAAAGGGGUCCUUUGGAGCCUUUGUUUAAAUAUGCCUUAGCCCCAGCUGCCCAUUUUUGGUUGACAAGCCUUUCAGAGCCAGAGUGGGUAUAGAUGUGCCAGCCAGGAGAUGGCACCGGAUGGCAGGUGUGCAAGGUGACAACUAGGAUAAUCAUGGCUGGAAUAAAGUAAGUUUCCACACUGGA